ACACAUUGUUUAGAGGCCGACGCGACACAGCCAUCUUGCGUCGGGGGCCCGGGCCCGGGAGGAGAGCGAGCCCCGUCCCCUGAUCCCGGAGGCCAACACCGGCGAGGGGCUGCCCUGCACGCAGGCGGCCGGCCCAGGAGUCUUAGCGGAUCAAGUUGUCUACGGCGGACUCGGGCCGGUCCCGCAGGACCCGGCCGCACUUGGCCGAGCGCGCAGGCGGGAAGGAGGCCGUCGGUCCGCCCCUCCCGCUGCCGCAGCGGCCAGCCGCCGCCGCGCCGCCGUCGCUCUCCAACGCCAGCGCCGCCUCUCGCUCGCCGAGCUCCAGCCGAAGGAGAAGGGGGUAAGGAGGUCUCUGUACCAUGGCUCGUACAAAGCAGACUGCCCGCAAAUCGACCGGUGGUAAAGCACCCAGGAAGCAACUGGCUACAAAAGCCGCUCGCAAGAGUGCGCCCUCUACUGGAGGGGUGAAGAAACCUCAUCGUUACAGGCCUGGUACUGUGGCGCUCCGUGAAAUUAGACGUUAUCAGAAGUCCACUGAACUUCUGAUUCGCAAACUUCCCUUCCAGCGUCUGGUGCGAGAAAUUGCUCAGGACUUUAAAACAGAUCUGCGCUUCCAGAGCGCAGCUAUCGGUGCUUUGCAGGAGGCAAGUGAGGCCUAUCUGGUUGGCCUUUUUGAAGACACCAACCUGUGUGCUAUCCAUGCCAAACGUGUAACAAUUAUGCCAAAAGACAUCCAGCUAGCACGCCGCAUACGUGGAGAACGUGCUUAAGAAUCCACUAUGAUGGGAAACAUUUCAUUCUCAAAAAAAAAAAAAAAAAUUUCUCUUCUUCCUGUUAUUGGUAGUUCUGAACGUUAGAUAUUUUUUUUCCAUGGGGUCAAAAGGUACCUAAGUAUAUGAUUGCGAGUGGAAAAAUAGGGGACAGAAAUCAGGUAUUGGCAGUUUUUCCAUUUUCAUUUGUGUGUGAAUUUUUAAUAUAAAUGCGGAGACGUAAAGCAUUAAUGCAAGUUAAAAUGUUUCAGUGAACAAGUUUCAGCGGUUCAACUUUAUAAUAAUUAUAAAUAAACCUGUUAAAUUUUUCUGGACAAUGCCAGCAUUUGGAUUUUUUUAAAACAAGUAAAUUUCUUAUUGAUGGCAACUAAAUGGUGUUUGUAGCAUUUUUAUCAUACAGUAGAUUCCAUCCAUUCACUAUACUUUUCUAACUGAGUUGUCCUACAUGCAAGUACAUGUUUUUAAUGUUGUCUGUCUUCUGUGCUGUUCCUGUAAGUUUGCUAUUAAAAUACAUUAAACUAUACCUGCUUUUGGUCUUUA